CUCUUUCGCUCAGGCCCGUGGCGCCGACAGGAUGGGCAAGUGUCGUGGACUUCGUACUGCUAGGAAGCUCCGUAGUCACCGACGAGACCAGAAGUGGCAUGAUAAACAGUAUAAGAAAGCUCAUUUGGGCACAGCCCUAAAGGCCAACCCUUUUGGAGGUGCUUCUCAUGCAAAAGGAAUCGUGCUGGAAAAAGUAGGAGUUGAAGCCAAACAGCCAAAUUCUGCCAUUAGGAAGUGUGUAAGGGUCCAGCUGAUCAAGAAUGGCAAGAAAAUCACAGCCUUUGUACCCAAUGACGGUUGCUUGAACUUUAUUGAGGAAAAUGAUGAAGUUCUGGUUGCUGGAUUUGGUCGCAAAGGUCAUGCUGUUGGUGAUAUUCCUGGAGUCCGCUUUAAGGUUGUCAAAGUAGCCAAUGUUUCUCUUUUGGCCCUAUACAAAGGCAAGAAGGAAAGACCAAGAUCAUAAAUAUUAAUGGUGAAAACACUGUAGUAAUAAAUUUUCAUAUGCCAAAAAAUGUUUGUAUCUUACUGUCCCCUGUUCUCACCACGAAGAUCAUGUUCAUUACCACCACCACCCCCCCUUAUUUUUUUUAUCCUAAACCAGCAAACGCAGGACCUGUACCAAUUUUAGGAGACAAUAAGACAGGGUUGUUUCAGGAUUCUCUAGAGUUAAUAACAUUUGUAACCUGGCACAGUUUCCCUCAUCCUGUGGAAUAAGAAAAUGGGAUAGAUCUGGAAUAAAUGUGCAGUAUUGUAGUAUUACUUUAAGAACUUUAAGGGAACUUCAAAAACUCACUGAAAUUCUAGUGAGAUACUUUCUUUUUUAUUCUUGGUAUUUUCCAUAUCGGGUGCAACACUUCAGUUACCAAAUUUCAUUGCACAUAGAUUAUCUUAGGUACCCUUGGAAAUGCACAUUCUUGUAUCCAUCUUACAGGGGCCCAAGAUGAUAAAUAGUAAACUCAAAAUUGCUCCCCACUCUGUUUAUUAUUUAAAGGUGUCAGGAUCUGUGUUGUAAUGUGUCUACAUUAAUGUGUUUAGGAGAAUACAGGCAUUGGAUCAUUUAGUUGAUGGAAGUAUAUGCCAGGCAAGGGAGAUAAGGUAUACGACAAGACUGAUGUUUUCAGUAUCUUCUCAUGAGGUUGUCAGAGACCUUCAUGUCUUCAAAGACUAGUCAGCAAAUGAAGUGGUUUAGUGUAGAGACAAGAUUGGUUGUGUUUUGAUAAUUUAAGCUAGGUAUUGAGUACAUGUGGAUUUUGCUGUCCACAAAUACUUGUUUCAGAGUUUUCAUGGAUACAGUGGCAUGGUUGAAAUGAAGCUGUGAGCCUUCUGCUUUAAAUCUGAUGUAAGAAACUCCUGUUAACAAAUAGUAAGUAUGGGUUAAUUAGCCCUUUGAUCAAAGCCUAGCUUUACAUUGUUUAGGAUCUUUGGAAAACAAUUGGUUUGGUUGCCCACUUUCCGUAGGAUCAAGAGCAGAACCUUUCACAUGGCACAGAAGAACCCAGGUUGCGCUUCAUACCUGCAUAUUCCAGCCUUAGCCUGCCAUUUCUCUCCUUGGCACUUUGUGCUCCAGCAACACUGGUCUCAGUUGGUCAUCCUCAAACUUGGGUUCCAUAUCCAGCCUCAGGACCUCUGUUCCUGUUACUAUGGUUCCUUGCAUGUCGCCUGCUCUUACUAAAGAGCUCGUGUGUUUUCCAGCACACUUCGGUUUAUCUCUUGAUGAUGAUGCUAGUCUCUCCCUCCGCAAGGGCGGAAAGGCUGCCUGUUGGUUUGUACCAGUGUUUCCUAACGUGUAGCUGCAGUCAGUAUUUGGCUAAGCUGUUCCCAGGGGCUCAACAGAUGCUUUCGGAUGAGCCUUAACUGACCCAAUCCUUUGUGAUGCGGGAGAGAUUGCUAGGCCUCGCUCACCUGGCCAGAACCAGGGAAAGAGGCCGCGGUUGCAGCGCGAUUCCAGGCCCUGGGCGUCAGGCGCGGGGUGGGCAGCUCUCCCCGGGCGGUGGGGCCCUUGUGACCGCGAGGCGGGGCGCACCAGGAAGGGAGUGGGACAGCGCGGGCGCCCAGGGAUGUGGCCUGGUUACCUGCCUUCUCUGAUACGUCAAGACACCUUCAACAAUGGCUUGCAGCUGUACCCUGUUGGCUGCACCCAGGACGCCCUUUUCACUGCUAAGCAGUCCUACCUGAGGCCCAGGGGCUGCCAGAUUGACCCAUAAAUAAUCUCCGGCGCCUCAGAUCCAGAAGCUGCUGAGCCUGAUCUUAGUGCCUUCUCCUUUCUCUGUGUGGCCCCCCAGCCCCUUUCCCCACUGCCUUGUGUCCAAGGCCCUUUCCUUCAUGUAUCCAUGGAGGAGAGACAAAAAUACACAUCAAUAAAAUAAGAUAGGGAAUCCAUAAAUAGACAUUCAGAAGUAUGGCCAACGGAUUUAUCUUAAAACCAAUGGAGGAAGAAGAGUUUCAAUAAAUGUUGUGGACUUCCAUUUGUCAAAGACCAAAACAAAGGAACCCCAACCUUACAUGUAAUACAAACUUAACUCAAAAUGGAUCAUAUAUCUAAAUGUAAAAUGGAAAGCUAUAAAACUGAAAACAGACUAUCUUUACAACCUAGGCGUAGGUAUAGUUUUUAGACAUUACACCAAAAGCACAUGCCGUAAAAGAAAAAAUAGAUAAAUUGGUGGAUUUCAUUAAAAUUAAAAAACUUUUUCUCUCUGAAAAAUCCUGUUAAGCUGGGCGCUGUGGUUCAUGCCUGUAAUCCCAGCACUUUGGGAGGCUGAGUUGGGAAGAAAUUAAUAGCUUGAGGCCAGGAGUUCAAGAUCAUCCUGGGCAGCAAAGUCAUACACUCUUGAGGGAAGAGAGAGACCUUCUCAUAUUGUUUUAUAUUGUUUUAUACUCAGUACCUGUUUUAAGAAAAAAACAAGGAAGUGAAAUCAAAGACAGGCAGCCCGGCACCAGGCCUGAAACCAGCCCUGGGCCUGCCUGGCCUAAACCUAGUAGUUAAAAAUCAACUUACGACUUAGAACCUGAUGUUAUCCGUAGAUUCCAAGCAUUGUAUAAAAAAAUUGUGAAACUCCCUGUUGUGUUCUGUACCAGUGCAUGAAACCCCUGUCACAUAUCCCCUAGAUUGCUCAAUCAAUCACGACCCUUUCAUGUGAAAUCUUUAGUGUUGUGAGCCCUUAAAAGGGACAGAAAUUGUGCACUUGAGGAGCUCAGAUUUUAAGGCUGUAGCUUGCCGAUGCUCCCAGCUGAAUAAAGCCCUUCCUUCUACAA